AAUAGCUGCCAUUGAUUGAUCACUUACUUUGUGUCAAGCAUUGUGCUUAGCAAUUUAUGUAAAUUAUUUCAUUUAAUCCUCCCACAAUAUCUAUAGGAGGUAGGUACUAUUUUACAAUGAGGAACCUGAGUUACUGAGAAGUUACAUUACUUACCUGAGGUCAUACAGCUAGUAAAUGUCAAAGCUGACCUUUAAAACCAGUUCUGUCUGACUUCAAAGCUCUCUCAAGUGCCCUUUUGGUUAUCUGGGGCCUUCCUGACAAGUGACUGUGCUGUAGUGGACUGAUUAUUUGUCUGCCCAGACUUUCUUCCUUUGGGCAGCUACUCUGUCCAAUUCAUGUGGUUUGGGUGGAGUUGACACUACCCAGGGAUGAUCAUGUGAUUCAGCCUUGGCCAAUCCGAGCAGUCCCUCCACUUGACCAAGGGAUUGGCUCAGGGGUUAGCAUGUGAUCCAGUCUGGCUCAAUGGGACUCUUCUGCUGGCAUUUAGGAAAGGGGGAGCUCUUCCUCUGGGAUUUAACCUGGAGCGAUGUAACCUGGAGCUACUGGUGGUCAUUUUUCCCUGCUCCAUGGAGGAAGCCGCAAUACAAGAGAAUGGGACCGUGCAGUGAGAAGCAGCACUGCACGGUGGUGAGAGCACACUCAGCAUUGUUUGAAGUGCAGGAGUCAGCUGUGCCAGGACUUCUCGAUUAUAAUACUGGGAUCUUCAGUGGCAGGAGGAGUAAUCAGAAGACGGAGAUGAAUUUUAACACUAUUUUGGAGGAGAUUCUUAUUAAAAGGUCACAGCAGAAAAAGAAGACAUCGCCCUUAAACUACAAAGAGAGACUUUUUGUACUUACAAAGUCCAUGCUAACCUACUAUGAGGGUCGAGCAGAGAAGAAAUACAGAAAGGGGUUUAUUGAUGUUUCAAAAAUCAAGUGUGUGGAAAUAGUGAAGAAUGAUGAUGGUGUCAUUCCCUGUCAAAAUAAGUAUCCAUUUCAGGUUGUUCAUGAUGCUAACACACUUUACAUUUUUGCACCUAGUCCACAAAGCAGGGACCUGUGGGUGAAGAAGUUAAAAGAAGAAAUAAAGAACAACAAUAAUAUUAUGAUUAAAUAUCAUCCUAAAUUCUGGACAGAUGGAAGUUAUCAGUGUUGUAGACAAACUGAAAAAUUAGCACCCGGAUGUGAAAAAUACAAUCUUUUUGAGAGCAGUAUAAGAAAAGCACUACCUCCAGCACCAGAAACAAAGAAGCGAAGGCCUCCCCCACCAAUUCCACUAGAAGAAGAAGAUAAUAGUGAAGAAAUCGUUGUAGCCAUGUAUGAUUUCCAAGCAGCAGAAGGACAUGAUCUCAGAUUAGAGAGAGGCCAAGAGUAUCUCAUUUUAGAAAAGAAUGAUGUUCAUUGGUGGAGAGCAAGAGAUAAAUAUGGGAAUGAAGGAUAUAUCCCAAGUAAUUACGUAACGGGAAAGAAAUCAAACAACUUAGAUCAAUAUGAAUGGUAUUGCAGAAAUAUGAAUAGAAGCAAGGCAGAGCAACUCCUCCGCAGUGAAGAUAAAGAAGGUGGUUUUAUGGUAAGGGAUUCCAGUCAACCAGGCUUGUACACAGUCUCCCUUUAUACCAAGUUUGGAGGAGAAGGUUCAUCGGGUUUUAGGCAUUAUCAUAUAAAGGAAACAACAACAUCUCCAAAGAAGUAUUACCUAGCUGAAAAACAUGCUUUUGGCUCCAUUCCUGAGAUUAUUGAAUAUCAUAAGCACAAUGCAGCAGGACUUGUCACCAGGCUUCGGUACCCAGUUAGUGUGAAAGGGAAGAAUGCACCCACCACUGCAGGAUUCAGCUAUGAGAAAUGGGAGAUUAACCCUUCAGAACUGACCUUUAUGAGGGAAUUGGGAAGUGGACUGUUUGGAGUGGUGAGGCUUGGCAAAUGGCGAGCCCAGUACAAAGUCGCAAUCAAAGCUAUUCGGGAAGGUGCAAUGUGCGAGGAGGACUUUAUAGAAGAAGCUAAAGUGAUGAUGAAACUGACACACCCGAAGUUAGUGCAGCUUUAUGGUGUGUGCACCCAGCAGAAACCAAUAUACAUUGUUACUGAGUUCAUGGAAAGGGGCUGCCUUCUGAAUUUCCUCCGACAGAGACAAGGUCAUUUCAGUAGAGACGUACUGCUGAGCAUGUGUCAGGAUGUGUGUGAAGGGAUGGAGUAUCUGGAGAGAAACAGCUUCAUCCACAGAGAUCUGGCUGCCAGAAAUUGUCUAGUAAGUGAGGCGGGAGUUGUAAAAGUAUCUGAUUUUGGAAUGGCCAGGUAUGUUCUGGAUGAUCAGUACACAAGUUCUUCUGGUGCUAAGUUUCCUGUGAAGUGGUGUCCACCUGAAGUGUUUAAUUACAGCCGCUUCAGCAGCAAAUCAGAUGUCUGGUCAUUUGGUGUUUUAAUGUGGGAAGUAUUCACGGAAGGCAGAAUGCCUUUUGAAAAAUACACCAAUUAUGAAGUGGUAACCAUGGUUACUCGAGGCCACCGACUCUACCAGCCGAAGUUGGCGUCCAACUAUGUGUAUGAGGUGAUGCUGAGAUGUUGGCAGGAGAAACCAGAGGGAAGGCCUUCUUUCGAAGAUCUGCUGCGCACAAUAGAUGAACUAGUUGAAUGUGAAGAAACUUUUGGAAGAUAAGUGAUGUGUGACCAGUGGCUCCCAGAUUCCCAAGCACAAGGAAGGAUGGGCAUUUUGUGGCUUUUAAUUUAUUGAGCACUUGGACAUGUAGAUCAUUUUACUUAUACAGUGGAAACACAUAAAUAAUUUGCUUCUAGACCAGCCUCUGUCUAGACUUGCUUCUAGACAGAAUCUCCCAGAGUGUGGAAAUGUUGCCUUAGAAAUGGUGAUUAAAAUCACUCAUUUCUAUUCAUUCCUCAGGCACUUGAGUGACAGUUGUUUACCAGGCACUGUGUGUAGCCCCAGGGUUUGGCCAUUCAGGGGUGCACACAUGGGACCAUGUUAGCUGAUGCCAGUUGAAGGCCAGGGUAUUUGGGAAGGGGAAGGGUAUUAGAGUCAUGACCAAGCAACCCUUCUUUUUCCCUUUGACUUCUACAGAAAUCUGGGCCUGAGACAUUGUCUACAAUUGGGUUCUAGAUACAUCAGGAACCCAUCUUGGAUAAAUAAAUACCUAUCUUUUGUUUUGAAAACAUCUCAGUUUUCAAGACUGCUCUUAGUAUUACAUGAACAAUAUUUGUAUGCUGUAUAUAUUGUAAAUAUAUAUAAUAUAUAAAGUUAUAUAUUUAUGAGAAACACGAAUUGUCUUUUAAUUGAAACUUUUAAUCCUGUAGUAUAGGAGUUCACCUUCUUAGGACUAGAGACUGUGCCUUAUAGCUGUUAAUUCAUUUCCCCCUGAACAUCAAAUAUGCCUGAAGAGAAGAAAGUCUAGAUUCUUCUAUGAGUAACGCCCCCUCCUCACUCAGGUAAAUGUGUCUGGGGAUGCCUGUCCAGCUUAACCACGUGCAUUUGGCCUAUGUAAUCCUGCCCAUGGUGGCCGCAGCUAAUCAGAAUCAGAUGGAAAAUUAAACCGGGUAAUCUACUUCUAAGCCUUAAGAAUAUUCCCUGGGACACAGACACUAUAAUUGGAAGUGCUGAGCUCUGGGGCAGAAGGAUCAGGUGACCUUCGCAACAAAGUUUGCCCCCACCUCACAUAGGACCCGGAAGCAGCCUGAGCUGUGGCGGAGGAUCCAGGAAGCUACGGAGAGAAGCAGCCAGCAUGGUGUUCCGUGCCUCCCGGACGUUUUUCAGGAGGCCUGGUUGGACUUGGGUUCCUGGAUGGUGGGAUUGUUGUACAGCCUCUCAGGAGACCCUGCUGUCAAGACUGUGUGUGUGGAUUUCUCACCCUUAGAAGCUCUACUAAGACAUCAACGGAAUUAGGGCCUUCCUUUUUGCCUUGUGAGCGCCAAGGAAAAGAAACUAUCUCGGUCACGUGAGCGCCAGCGAAAAGAAACUGUAUCAGUCAUCCAGAGACCGUUUAUUGCCCAACACGUUAUUCUUGCUGUUGGUGGGGUAACUAGCCGAGGAAGACACAGCGCCUUCCCUUCAGGAGUUGCGUCUCCUCUGCAGGCCACGAUGGUCUGCUCUGGAGCAUUGGGUGAACACACAGGCUGGCUGCUCUGGGCAGCGCCUUCACUCUGACCCUGGAGAACCAUUUCAUUUCAUCCUGGUCAGUCUAGAGUCUGUGCACCAGGCAGUCCAUCCACUGAAGGCUGUGUUUAUUCUUUUCCUGUGCCCCUCAUAAUGGAAGAAAGUAAACUGCUUAUCCCGAGCCUUA